AUGUCUCUCGCCGUCUCCAGCCUCAGUCCCUCUCUGUCUCUCUCUCAGUCUCUCUCCCUGUCCUCCCCGGCCGCUCCUCCGAGAUGACGCCGGGGUCGGUGCCCCGGGCCUGCCCUAUCCCCUGGCUCCAGGGCUAGGCGGGACCGAGGGCUGCCCCAGACAGACGGACCCGCGGACCCACAGACCCCGCGCCCAGGAGAGGAGCCGCGCCGCCCGCCGCUGGCAGCCCGUCACCAUGGACCCUCCAUCCCUCGACACAGCCAUCCAGCAUGCCCUGGCGGGCCUCUAUCCUCCUUUCGAGGCCACAGCACCCACCGUCCUGGGUCAGGUGUUCCGUCUCCUGGACUCUGGCUUCCAGGGGGAUGGGCUGAGCUUCCUUCUGGAUUUCCUGAUCCCUGCCAAGCGCCUGUGUGAGCAAGUGCGAGAAGCAGCCUGUGCUCCCUACUCACACUGCCUCUUCUUACACGAGGGCUGGCCACUCUGUCUGAGGGAUGAAGUUGUGGUCCACUUGGCACCCCUCAACCCUCUCUUAUUGCGCCAGGGUGACUUCUACCUCCAAGUGGAGCCCCAGGAGGAGCAGUCUGUCUGCAUCAUGAUCAAAUGCCUCUCCCUGGACCUCUGCACAGUGGACAAGAAGCCUGUUCCAGAGCCAGCCUACCCUAUACUUUUCACCCAAGAAUGGCUGGAGGCCAUCAACAGUGACUUUGAGGGAAAUCCCCUACACAACUGCUUGGUAGCAUCAGAAAAUGGGAUUGCCCCUGUGCCUUGGACCAAGAUAACCAGCCCAGAGUUUGUGGAUGACAGACCCCAAGUAGUGAAUGCCCUCUGCCAAGCCUGGGGGCCCCUUCCAUUAGAGGCACUGGAUUUGAGCAGCCCUCAAGAGUUGCACCAGGCCAGCUCCCCAGACAACCAGGUGCUUCCUGCCCAGAGUUUGGCCAAGGGUAAGGGCAGGACAUAUGGGAGCAAGUAUCCAGGACUCAUCAAGGUGGAGCAAGCCCGGUGUGGGGAGGUGGCUUUCAGGAUGGACGAGGUGGUCAGCCAGGACUUCGAGGGAGACUAUGUGGCUCUCCUAGGCUUUUCCCAAGAGAGCAGAGGAGAGUCUCCCAGUAGGGAGGCAGGCACAUCCAGUGGGUGUACUUCUGGGGCACUAGAGGAGAUAGCUGGAACUAAGGAAACUCCCUUAUUUCAAAAGAUACUGCCUCUCUCAGAGGCCAAUGAAGGACCUUCCUUGGGAAAUCGGGCUUGCACAAAGCCAGAAAGCUCUGAGGAGAGGCCCUAUAAUUUGGGCUUCAGGAGAAAGGUCAAUCUUAAAGCACCCACCCACAACUCAGAAAGGCCGCCCCAAGGCUCCUACAUGAAUGUCCUUGAGGACGCACUGGACUGUGCCUCUGGUCUCAGGGCAGGUGUCUCACAAGAGCCAGCUGCCUCCAAGAUGCAGGGACCUCUAGGAAACCCAGAGAAUAUGGUGCAGCUCAGGCCUGGACCAAGACAAGCCUCCUCUCCCCGCCUGUCCCCAGCUUCUCCUGCAGCUGCAGCCUCUGAAACAAAGAUAGAGGUGAAGACCAAAGAGAGAAAUGGGAGACUUCCCAAGCCCAUGCCCUGCCCUAGCAGAAACACCUCCUCCCCUGAGCCCCCCACUCCUGGGCUCAAAUUCUCAUUCUUGAGAGGGCAGAGGCAACCCUCUGUGACCCCGGAGAAAGCCUCACUCCAGCACAAUGGGCCCUGGAAAGUCCUGUGUUCCCUCUACUCUCCUAAACCCAACCGAGCCAAAUCUUUGGGGAAAGCUGGAACAACUCAGACCAAAACAUCUGGCCCAGCCACUGCCCCCAGCCCACUGACUGAGGAAAAGGCUGCCUUGCCAGAAGCUUCUGCAGGCUCCCCAGAAAGAGGCCCCACCCUGGAGGAGGAGCCCCCAGGGCCUGAGCCCAGGAUUGGGGCUCUAGGUGUCAAGGUUUUCCGCUCCAGGAUAGCAUGCCUGCCAGGUGGCCGGGACAGGGCCGGGCGGCCCCUGCUUCUGGUGUCAACUACAGAGGGGGCCUGGGAGGCACCAUGGUGCACAGUUUCAGAGGUCACCAAGCUACUGUCCUACCUGUGUACCAUCCCCAGGCCUGAAGAUAAAGCCAAGGGGCUGGCGGUCCUGAUUGACGCCAGGAGACAGCCCCCACAGCCCGGUCUGGUCAGCGCCCUGCAGGCCACCCAGGCUCAGGUCCCAGCCUCUAUCCGGGCUAUUCUCUUCCUGGGGGAGAAGGAGGCGGCUCUCCAGCUGCAGACAUUACCUGACGUCCAGGUGGAGGUGCUGACCUCAUUGAAGGCCCUCAGCCACCAUGUGGACCCCAGCCAGCUGCCCGCAGUCCUGGAAGGCCCCUUCCCCUACUGCCACACCGAGUGGGUUCAUUUCUUCCAGAAGCUGGACCCUUUCCUUGCUGACCUCCACCAGGCCUCUUCCCUGCUACAAGCUUCCAUCGAGGAAUUCGAGAAGGCCGACCCCCCUGGGGGGAUGCAGGAGGCUACCAGGUGCCUGAGCAAGUCCAAGGAGCUGAUGGAGGCUGUGCUGAGGGACCCCGGCCUACUGGGCCUCCAGCGGGAAGGUGGAGCCACCCUGGCCAGGCUGCAGCAUGAUGCCAGCAGGCUGGACUUCAGCCCUGAUGUCAGGAGCCAUCUGGCUGCAGCCACUGCCUUGUACAGCCUUGUGGACGAGCAGCUUCAUGUUCUGGUCACCGCUUCCAACAGCCUCCUGGGGAAGCUGGAGCUCCGUGUCCGCCUGGGCCGCCUGGAAGCUGCCAUUCACCAGGUCAGCGACUGGAUGGAGCAGGAAGGAAGGCGGUGCCUGCAAUCACUGACCCCCAAGGAUGGAAGUUUGGAGACAGUGGAGAAAGCCCACGCAGAAUUUGAGAACUUCUUCCUCCAGGCUGCAGCCCAGUACCGCCGAGGCCUGGAGCUGUCCAAGCAGGCCGCUCAGCUGGGAGCUACAGCCAGAGGGGCUGGGGAGGCAGAACGUGCAGAGUUCCCAGAGCUGGCAGCCUUUGCCUCUACCCAGCGGGCCUUCCAGGCUGAGCUGACCCACUUUUACAUGGCGGCCGAGCGGCAACGCACGGACCUCGAGACGCUGCUCCACCUGCACCGCUUCUGCAAGAGGUCUUGUAACAGGAAAAAAACAGAGGAAGGGGAAGAGCUGAGAUUUGAACAUAGAUGUGUCUGUGGUACCCCGUGACAUGCCUUAUAUGCUUCCCCAAAGAGAAGAGAAAUGACGACAGAUCCCUUCACCAAGCAGGCUUGACCAUGGUGAGGAUGAGGGGUUGUUGGGAGGGGAGUGCACAUUUCUGAGUGUGUACACCAUGCCAGACCUCCUGUGAGCACUUCACACACCUUACUUGACUUCAUUCUUAUCCAUACCUCUUUGAUGACAGGGAACCAAUGUUGUUCCCAUUUUACAGAUGAGAAAACUGCCCAAAGAGGGCAGUGGUGAAGGAUGAUUUGAUUUAGGAGCUGCCACCUGUCCUAAAUUCAUGUAGCCAAAUCUCUCUUUAAAAAAAAAUUAUGGGAAAACUGAGGUCUGUGGGGACAAAGGAGCAGCCUGGGAGAGUGUGGUCCAGCUGGGACAGGGACCCCCAUGGCUGGCCCAGACCCAGUGCCCUUGGCUGCCCCUUGCACUUGUCACCAAGGACAAAGCAUGAGAAAGACCUGACCCCAGCCUCCCAGCUGUCAGGCCAGCCCCACGUGCAGGCCACAGCGAUCACAGGCUGCUUCAGAGGGCAGCAGGAGGGACUCUGGUCAACUCACGCCUGGGGCCCUGGGAGGACAGGGCACUCUCUGUCUCCUUGGGACAGUGGGCAAGGGAGGCAGAUGUUGGCAGUGGCAGCAAAGGGCUCCCCCAGUUCCAGCUGUGUACAGUUAAGAGCACGAUACAGGCGGAAUCCGAGCCUUGGAGUCUGGGGCUUCAUGUCCUUGCGUGAGCUCUGUGACCUCAACCACAGUCUUCACUGCUCUAGGCCUCAGCUCUUUGCUAAGACCAUAGUUAAUGGCCGUGUAGUUCUUAUGACAAGCCAGGCCCUGUUCUAGUCAUUUCACGUAUCAUUUUAUUGUCGCCCCGAUCCUAUGAGACAGGUACUACUAUUAUGCCCAUUUCCACCUAAGGAAACAGAGAGGUCAGAUAACUCACCCAGGGUCACACAGCUAACUGAGUGGGCAGAGAUUCAAACCCAGACCAUCUGGCUCUACUGCCAGCCUUACCAGCUAAUGACAGAUUUCAAUGGAAGUAACCCCUGGCACAGGGCUUUGUUCAAAUUCAGAAUUGUUAUUAACAUCAAUAUUAUUAUUAUCAUUAAGAGGAGGAAGAAGAGGAGUAGUGCCUCCAGGGUUAAAGACAUCUGGUAGCUUCUUUGCCUUGCCCACUGAUUUCAGCCAAUUUCAGCCCCACUGGCCUUCCCGGAUCGAUCAAACGUGCUCCAACUCUGAGGUCUUUGCACGUGCUGUUCCCUCAGCCUGGGAAGCUCUUCCCGUUGACCGGCUGGCUUCUUGUCUUUCUUCCGCUCUCAGCUCACACAUCCCCUCUUUGCAGACACCCUUUCUGACUGCCCACUCUGGUUCUCUCUCGUCACCCUGUUUUGUCGCUUCUGGGUGCUCACUUUGACCUGAAGUUGUCCUGGUCCUUGUCACUCGCUUGUCUCUUGCAUGGUGCCUGCGAGGCGAGCUCCCUGAGACAGGGACUGGGUUCGAGUUGGUCCUGGCUCUAUCCAUGGUGCCUGGCACGGGCUCGGCCCACAAGGUCUCAGGGAGGCUGUGCGGGGAGUCAGGAUAGGCUGGAAGCCUGGGGAUGGCCUGUGUGGAGGUGGCGUCUGUGCCAGGCCUAGAAGUCAUACGGGGGAGGUAGCAACCCUGACUCUGAGUCCAACUCUCGCUGUUGGAACUGGGCUGGCCCUGUUUCCUCACUGGCCCUGAAUUUCAAUCCGUUCAAUAAGGGGUUGGGCAAGAUGAUUUCUGAGGUGCUAUCCAUCUCUGUCCAGCUUAGCCUGGAAGGUCAAGUCCUGGACACACAGACAGAUGAUGGGACAGCCCAGCACCAGGCUCAGCCCCUGGUGGGGAGCGUGUGUGCAGCAGCUUUGGUCCUAAAUAAUAAUAACACAAUGGUGCCACUAACGGAGAUUUAUGGAGCUCUUUCCCGGCCAUGAGCUCCGUGUGCUUGCACGAAUAUGAAGCCAUUUAUCUAAAGUCAAGUUCCCUUAAUCCGUGGAAAGAUGGUCUCUUCGGAGAAAAUGGUUCUCCAAUCCCUACAGCCUAACAGCUCGCUAUCGGGUUCUAAAUUAAUGGAGAGAAAGAUUAUGUUUUUCACGAGCGGCUGGGAACGUGUUGGCUUCUUUGCAGUCUGCAGACGUUUUGUGGGGGAAGCGGGGACAGACAGAAUCACAAAAUGAGGCAGAGGCUCGGCUGGAGGGAGGGGGCCUGCGGGCCUGGUGUGGCUGACAGUCUCAAGGUGUGAUGGUGAGGGCACACCCCUGCCUGGCCGGUUUCUCCUUCUGCCCAUGAAGGUGCUUGGAGGACAGAUCAGAGGUGGAAUCCCAGCUCCUCCCUGACUUGCUAUGUGACCUAGGGCAAGUGAGUUCACUUCUCUGAGCCUCAGUUUUCUUCUCUGUGAAAUGGGCUGCUGGUGCAGUUCAGUGCAAUCCUGCCUGAGACACACAGAACCUGGCAAACGGUCAGUGCUCAAUAAGCAUUAGGCAGACUCCUCCCUCACAGCACUCUCAAGGGUUAAUACAACCAUGGAGAGGAAUUUCACCUCUCAAAAGGCUUUUCAUGAUCAUCUAGUGCAACUUCCAUUUUACAGAAGAAGAAACUGAGCCCCAGAGAGGGCUAAGUCCCUGCUGGCCCGUAGGUCUAUUAGAAGGUGUCUGAUGGGCUGGGCGCAGUGGGUCAUGCCUAUAAUCCCAGCACUUUGGGAGGCUGCGGCGGGUGGAUCACCUGAGGUCAGGAGUUCGAGACCAGCCUGACCAACAAGGUGAAACCCCGUCCUACUAAAAAUACAAAAAUUAGCUGGGCAUGGCAGCAGGUGCCUAUAGCCUCAGCUACUCGGGAGGCUGAGACAGGAGAAUUGUUUGAACCUGGGAAGCAGAGCUUGCAGUGAGCCGAGAUCACACCACUGCACUCUAGCCUGGGUGAUGGAGCGAGACUCCAUCUCAAAAAAAAAAAAAAGGUGUCUGAUGAUUCUAAGGGUGCUUGGGGGCUGUUUCCAGAUGGCAGGUGUGUGCACCCCAGGGAAGAGAGGGAAACCAGGGUCAUCAUGGUCAGUGGAGAAGAUCAUGGCCAAGCUGAGCGGGGCCCUGGCAUUGGGCACUUAUUAAUUCAGUCCUCCAUGGUCCCACUUCCAGCCUGAGCCCCCACCUCCCUCUCUUCUUGUC